GCUUUUGCAAGGCUGUGGUCGGUGGUCAUCAGUGCUCUUGACCCAGGUCCAGCGAGCCUUUUCCCUGGUGUUGCAGCUGUUGUUGUACCGCCGCCGUCGCCGCCGUCGCCGCCUGCUCUGCGGGGUCAUGGUGUGCUUCCGCCUCUUCCCGGUUCCGGGCUCAGGGCUCGUUCUGGUCUGCCUAGUCCUGGGAGCUGUGCGGUCUUAUGCAUUGGAACUUAAUUUGACAGAUUCAGAAAAUGCCACUUGCCUUUAUGCAAAAUGGCAGAUGAAUUUCACAGUACGCUAUGAAACUACAAAUAAAACUUAUAAAACUGUAACCAUUUCAGACCAUGGCACUGUGACAUAUAAUGGAAGCAUUUGUGGGGAUGAUCAGAAUGGUCCCAAAAUAGCAGUGCAGUUCGGACCUGGCUUUUCCUGGAUUGCGAAUUUUACCAAGGCAGCAUCUACUUAUUCAAUUGACAGCGUCUCAUUUUCCUACAACACUGGUGAUAACACAACAUUUCCUGAUGCUGAAGAUAAAGGAAUUCUUACUGUUGAUGAACUUUUGGCCAUCAGAAUUCCAUUGAAUGACCUUUUUAGAUGCAAUAGUUUAUCAACUUUGGAAAAGAAUGAUGUUGUCCAACACUACUGGGAUGUUCUUGUACAAGCUUUUGUCCAAAAUGGCACAGUGAGCACAAAUGAGUUCCUGUGUGAUAAAGACAAAACUUCAACAGUGGCACCCACCAUACACACCACUGUGCCAUCUCCUACUACAACACCUACUCCAAAGGAAAAACCAGAAGCUGGAACCUAUUCAGUUAAUAAUGGCAAUGAUACUUGUCUGCUGGCUACCAUGGGGCUGCAGCUGAACAUCACUCAGGAUAAGGUUGCUUCAGUUAUUAACAUCAACCCCAAUACAACUCACUCCACAGGCAGCUGCCGUUCUCACACUGCUCUACUUAGACUCAAUAGCAGCACCAUUAAGUAUCUAGACUUUGUCUUUGCUGUGAAAAAUGAAAACCGAUUUUAUCUGAAGGAAGUGAACAUCAGCAUGUAUUUGGUUAAUGGCUCCGUUUUCAGCAUUGCAAAUAACAAUCUCAGCUACUGGGAUGCCCCCCUGGGAAGUUCUUAUAUGUGCAACAAAGAGCAGACUGUUUCAGUGUCUGGAGCAUUUCAGAUAAAUACCUUUGAUCUAAGGGUUCAGCCUUUCAAUGUGACACAAGGAAAGUAUUCUACAGCUCAAGACUGCAGUGCAGAUGACGACAACUUCCUUGUGCCCAUAGCGGUGGGAGCUGCCUUGGCAGGAGUACUUAUUCUAGUGUUGCUGGCUUAUUUUAUUGGUCUCAAGCACCAUCAUGCUGGAUAUGAGCAAUUUUAGAAUCUGCAACCUGAUUGAUUAUAUAAAAAUACAUGCAAAUAACAAGAUUUUCUUACCUCUCAGUUGUUGAAACACUUUGCUUCUUAAAAUUGAUAUGUUGAAACUUUAAUUCUUUUAUCAAUCCCAGCAUUUUGAGAUCAGUCUUUAUUAAUAAAACCUGUUCUCUUUAAUCAGCUUAAAAUCCAAAGUGUCAUAUUUACUGGUCCUGGAGACAAACUUGUUCAAAAGAACAUCAACGUGCAAUGUUUUAAGGUCUAUCUUAAGAAGCCCUGGCCAAAUUUUGAUCCUAACCUUGAAGUAUGCCUUGAACUUAUUAACAUGGCCAUUAUAAGAAUAAAAUAUGUAGUUGUGUCUUAAUGGAAUUAAUAAAUGUCAUUUCACUACUGGUGUUCUGUUUCAAUGUAUAAGGACUAUAGUGAUUUAAACUCAUCAAUGUGCCUUUGCAUAAAGUUCAUUAAAUAAAUAUUGAUGUGGUAUAAAUGCCCAUCAGAUAUGCUUAAACUUGGUUUUCAGUUGAAUGAAGUAGAGAAUGUCCUCAGGACCAUCAGCAUUUUAAAGGUUAUGUGACUUUUGCUGAUUUCUCUGAGUUCAAGUUAAGCAUGAAGUUAGUACCUCAAGCCUGUGAUUUUUCCCUAGGGAUGAUACAGACCCAAGAGGCUACAACAGAACUUAAACUGGCUUCGUAAUUAGAGUUUUUAAGAUAAUUGUUUGUUUUUCAGCAAUAUAGACUGAAAAGAUCCAAGCAUAUUUAGCCACUUGCUUUUUUGUUUCUUGUUUUGUUCUUCUUUGGAUGCCUGAUUAGUAUUGAAAGAUAGAAAUAUUCUAUGAACUAAUUAGGACAGAUUGUGUUGUGUUUCUCUACCUCAUCUUGUUGAUCUCUGGAGCAUUAAAAUCUAUUUAGUGUUGUCAUCAGUGUGGUACUUAUGAAAUGUAAGCUAACAGCAAUCUCAGAAGGGAGGCAGUGAAGCAUAGCAACUAGGCUCUUGUUUCUUCAAGAUGGCCCCUGUGGGGCAGUGCAUAGAUGGGGGUGUAAAGAGAAGCUGUUGGCAUUAAAAUGAGCUAGAUAAUCAGCCCUUGUUGAAGCAUAUUCCAUGGUAUAAGAGUAGCACAGACAUGAAACAUAGAUAAAGAAGGAAGGCUUAAUAGACUAGAAGACUUCCACAUUGAAGUAUUAUUAACCCAUUGUAUGUAUAUAGGGGCAUGAUCAGAGUCUCUAUAACUUCCUGAUUAACAAUACAGUGUAUCUUGUUACCCAGCUGUCAGUCUUUGAGAGCUUUCAGUAAAAUAUAGUAAAUUCUUUCAGCAUAGGCUAAUGUGUGGUUACUGAGAUGAGUGUUGUGUACUCAGAACCGUAGCAACAUUUUUAUGAAUGGUAAAAGUACAAGAGGAGGAAAAGUUAAAAUUAGAAGAAAAGUACAAGUUAUUGCUUAAUCAUAAAUCACACCAGAUAACACAUUUUGUUAAUUUCAUUAGCUAUUACUGGAAAGGACCUUAACGAUUAUUUACAGAAAGGGGAGUGAAAUUCAUUGAGGUUCCAUAUCAAGUGGGCAACAAAACUAUUACUAGCAUUUUGAUAAAAAUUGCCCCUAAUGAAAUCUAGUCACUCAACAGUAAAACAACAGCUGGUUUACACUUGAAAUUAUGAGAUCAGAAUUGGGCACUUUGGGCUUCCGUACUAUGUUUUGCUUAAGUUUUUUUUUUAAUACUAAUAUGGGCUUUUUCAGUAGUAAUAUACCAAAACACUUCUAUUUUAAUCUCUGUUUGCUACUUCAAAACCUAAUCCUCCUCAGAUGGGAUCAUGAGCAUAAGAGGAAAAGAGAAGAGAAUGAAUACUUGUUGACCUCUUGAUGUGUAUCAGAUGCUUUAGAAAUGUAAUUGUAUUUAAUCCUCAAAUACCUUAUAGGUAUUAUUAUCCCCUUCUUACAGAUGAGGAAAGUGAGGCCCAGUUUAAAUAACUUGCCCAAGGUCCUUUGGCUAGUACUGGAAGGAGUCAAGAUUUAAACACAGUUCUGUCUGAAUCCAGAACUCAAAAUCUACAUUGCACAUGUUGCUUUCCUGGUGGUUCGGUGGAAUGGACUGCAACGCAUUAGAUACUGCUGUUAUUCUUCCAGGCCACCGCUCAGCUAAAAAUAAUUGUGUGUGUGUGUAUAUAUAUAUAUAUGUACACACACACACAUAUAUAUACACACACACAUAUAUAUACACAUAUACAUAUAUAUACACAUAUAUAUACACACACAUAUAUAUGUAUAUAUAUACUACAUUCUUGAUCCUAAGUCUUUUUUAACUUAAAUUUUAUUACUUAUACAGAAUUCUUAUUUAUACUUUAAUUAUAGGUGUGACGAAGAGAAAGAGAGUAGGGAAAUACACAGGCAGUGGUUUUAAGUGUAGAUGAUGGCUCCUUAACCCAGUGUCAUUAGAUAAUCAAACCUAAAGUCUUCCCAUAUUAGGCAAGCGCAAUUCUCUAUUUUGGACCCUUCCCAUUCUUCCCUUACCUUCUGCUUUUCGUACUGAGGAAUUUCGUGUGAUUUUAGAUAAAGUGAUAAUGAGAUAUUGAGCAAAUAAGAAAAUAGAGGUAAUGCUAUAAAAAACUAAGCUAUGUACACUUUCAAAAUGCAUGUUUCUUGCAUGCUUUUUACUACUUAAUUGCAUUCUUUGCUAAUUUCCUUUCCUUGCUGUCUGUUCUUUUCUAACAGCUGAAGAAUGUUCUGCUGACUCUGACCUCAACUUUCUUAUUCCUGUUGCAGUGGGUGUGGCCUUGGGCUUCCUUAUAAUUGUUGUCUUUAUCUCUUAUAUGAUUGGAAGAAGGAAAAGUCGUACUGGUUAUCAGUCUGUGUAAUCAGUUAAAUCUAGUGUUUGUUUGUUUUUUUCAAUUAGAAGUUACGUUUCCAUUGGCUAAAAGCCAGGACAUGCUGUGCAAUAGAUUGUUUAAGAUAUGCAGACUAACUUCAGUGAGUUCCUAGCUAACUUGGGCAUGAGUACACUUAUUUAAGACAAAAUAUAUUAGGACCAAUUUUUUUCUGUUUUUUUUCUUCCUUUGUUAAAGUAUAAUUAAAAGAAAAAUUGUGGCUUAGAAUUUUUUAAGUAAAUAAUGAUUUUAAGCCCCUGGAUCCAAUUAUGAAAGCAUUUUUGCUGAUGUGUAAUUUUAUAUGUUACAGUUACUUAUAUUUUACUACUUUGAUGUUAUUUGCAAAAUCAAAGGUGUUAAAGAAUUUAACUUGCUUCAGGAAAUAAAUUCAAGAACAUAGUGGAUUCAUUUUCAUUGGUGGCAGACACGAAAUUUGGUUCAUGAUAAGACUUCCUUUCCCCACCUCCUGAUCAGCAUUAUUUAAAUCUGUAUUUUUCUGUUAGUUAAGAAAGAAAUGGCUUCAUGAUAUUGUAUUUAAUAGCAAAAGUUUGGCUGUCUUCUUCAUUACUGUUAAUAGCUACUAUAUUUUAACAAGGAGAUUUCUUUUUUUGUUGUUGUUGUUCUAGAGUUUGGAAUAUACUGAUUAUCUCAGACUUGACAUUUAUACUGAAGGAUGAAGUAAGACCUCCAGCUUUUUUUAAAAAAGGUGUUGAUUUGGAACACCUGUAUGGGUUAUGGUUUAUUAAGGUUAUGGUUUAGAAAGUUUUUUUCCCUCAGAGCCUUAACUUGUUAAGAAGGUUCAUUUAUCCUGCACUGAAAACAAAAACUCUAUAUACUUUGUUUGUGUGCCUCCUGCACUCUCCCAUUCCCUAUGUGAAUAUGCUCUAGUUGAUAUUUUUAAUAUAUUGAUUUCUUUUUUCUCACAGCAACAAGUGCUUACUCUAGAGGUUAGUGGGCCCUGAUAUGUCAUCAGUCAGAUGCCUGCCUAGCCAAAGCUGGACUAAGAUUAUUCUGUACAUUUGUUGAUCUUGAUAUAGACUUAUAUCCCUGUAGGGACUGCUAAUGGCUCCGGCUUCUGGAGUAAGGUACUGGAGACCACUCAUCCCUGUGUCUGCUUGAUUGGUUCAGCUGUUGAAUUGCCCUUUUAUUUGGAAGCAGUGUUGAAGUUGUCUAGGGUUCAAAUGGCUGCUUUGUACACCUGUCAUUAGUAUAAGGCAGAUGUUUAUUUUAUCAAGCUAUUUUAUCUCUACAUUUAACUAAAAACAAAAGUUCCCAAAGAUCUGCCUUCACUUCAGAAAUUUUUUUUGGAUUAAAAAAAUUAAGCCUGAACCUUAAAUAAAGUGAGUUGGUUAUUCAUUCCAAGGAUUAAGUCCCAAUCUACCUCUCAGCACAAUGCAGAAGCUCACCACUGUAUUGCUGCCAUUAACUCAUGCCAGAACCCUUUGCCAAUAACUGGAAUUACAAAUUUUUGUUAAAGAAAAUUUAUCAAGAUCUUUCUUUACUGCCUUCUCUAUAUGUACAUCUCAAAAACAUGUACAUCUCAAAAACUGGAGUAGAAAGUUAGAUUGCUCAACUACAACUCCUCUAGAACUCUAUAGCUCUGACAUACAGAUUCACACUCUCCUCUAUUUGCUAAGUAUGUAAAGAAUGUUUUCUUUUAAAAUGUUCUCUUUUGAGAACAACUGCUUAUUUGUUAUAAAAGCAUUUGGUUAAAAUGAUGUCAUCAUAAAAAACAGUGGCUUUGUUUCAAUACAUAUUUUUGAGAUGAUUAUCUAGAAGCCAGAUUAAUAAAAUCAGCUUGUGACCUUGCUAAGCAUAUAAACUGGAAAUUCAGAUACAUUCAAAAUUAUGGGUUCAUUUAAAAGUGUUCUACCUUUUGGGUAUGAGACUAAUAUCACUAAUUCCUCAAUAGUUAUCAUGGCUCUAUCUUAAUUAAUUAGAAAAUAUGUGUGUUUAAUUCUUUGAGAAUUAAAAUAGAGAAUAUUAACAGAGGGUUAAAAACUGCUUCAACUCCAAUAAGAUAAAGGAAGCUCAAAAUCUAUGAGCUGAGUGUUCAAUUAGCUUUGCCUACUGAGUUCAAUUUUAUGUCAAUACAACAGUGGAUCAGACAGUACGACUUUGAACUGGUGAAUGUAAACAAUUGUUUUUCACCUAAGCUGCUUUGGAAGAACUGAUGCUUGCUGCUAACUAAAGUUUUGGAUGUAUCGAUUUAGAGAACCAAUUAAUACCUGCAAAAUAAAGCAUACUGUGGUACUUCUGUUUGAUCUAGUAUGUGUGAUUUUAGAUUGAUGGAUUAAAAAUUAAUAAAGAUCAUACAUUCCAUACCA